GGUCACAAGGUAUACGCCCUUCUCCUCUUUCCACGCUUCUCGAGAGGCUCCCGCGGCCAGAACCGGAAAACAAGGAGUAACAGUCGCGUUUCAAAUCUCGCAGACCUGCUGGCCGAUUUCGAGUCUUCUGAAAGAGGAAGGCGAGCAAAGCCAAAAUUCUCCCAGAGCGCGAACCCAAACACAGAUCGCCGCUGGGGUCCAAGCGCCCUUCAACUCCGCCCGCUAGUGCCCAAGAUUACCGGGAAGGAAUUCAACGAAUCAGUGGUGAGGUGCCGCCGCCAUGCCUACUACGGGCGGAAAUUUGAGAGAAAGCUUCGCACCGGUAGGAAAACUGAGGAGCAACCGAGCACGAUUGGAAAGGUUGACGAUAGUGGUUAAGUGGCUCGGCCUUGCCCUCAGUUAAAAUGGCAAUUUUAGUUGCUUCACUGAUACGGAAUCGGCGAGGCGCCAAGGAGGCUUCCUGCGUGGGGCCGCAGAGCGAGUCGGGAAACGAUUUUAAACUGAAGAGGCGGCGGAGGGCCGAAUUCCCUUUUCUCAACGGCUUGAUUUCAGAGCUGGGCUGGUCUCUGACAGGCUCAGCUGGAGAGGGACGGGUUGGGACGCACUGUCCUUUUGCCCUUCCCCCUCCGCGAGCAGAAGCUGACUCCGCAGGAGCGAGGGUCGCAGAGCUGGGUGAGCGGAAAUGUCCCUCCCAGAGUGAAGUCGCAGGGCCCGCCCCGCGUCUGAGGGAGCGGAGGUCUUCCUGGGUGCGUUUGUGUCUCUUGUGAACCCACUUGUGGAGCGAGAGGGAAUUUGGGAGGGCCAGGGGUUAGUCUGGCCUCUGUCUUAGCUGUCAUUUUGGCGGUUUUUUUUUUUUUUCUUCAGGGGAUUUCAGUCUCCACAUAGUUUUGGAGCCGGACUUUUGAAGAAUGAUUCGUGAAUCCGGAAUGGGUGACAGCGUCAUCACGGCAUUUUAUUGACAGACCAUGGAUUCUUACAGUGCACCAGAGUCAACUCCUAGUGCAUCCUCAAGACCUGAAGAUUACUUUAUAGGUGCCACUCCUCUGCAGAAACGAUUAGAAUCGGUCAGGAAGCAGAGUUCAUUUAUCCUGACUCCACCUCGAAGGAAAAUUCCCCAGUGUUCGCAGUUGCAGGAAGAUGUUGACCCUCAAAAGGUUGCAUUCCUUCUGCAUAAACAGUGGACUUUAUAUAGUUUAACUCCCUUAUAUAAAUUCUCCUAUAGUAAUCUCAAAGAGUAUUCUAGACUUCUCAAUGCUUUUAUUGUUGCUGAAAAGCAAAAAGGACUUGCUGUGGAAGUGGGAGAAGACUUCAACAUCAAAGUGAUUUUUUCUACUCUCCUAGGAAUGAAAGGAACACAAAGGGACCCGGAAGCAUUUCUUGUCCAGGGUCUCAUUUUGUCACCCAGGCUGGAGUACAGUGGCACGAUCUUGGUUGACUGCAACCUCUGUCUCCUGGGCUCAAGUGAUCCUUCCACCUUAGCCUUCCAAGUAGCUGGGACUGCAGGUGCAUGCCACCACACUCGGAUUGUGUCAAAAUCUCAAUUGCCAUCUGAGAAUAGAGAAGGUAAAGUGCUGUGGACUGGCUGGUUCUGCUGUGUAUUUGGAGACAGUCUUCUGGAGACUGUUUCAGAAGAUUUCACCUGUCUGCCCUUAUUCCUUGCAAAUGGAGCAGAGUCUAACACAGCAAUAAUUGGAACUUGGUUUCAGAAAACCUUUGACUGUUAUUUCAGUCCUUUAGCAAUCAAUGCAUUUAAUCUUUCCUGGAUGGCUGCCAUGUGGACUGCAUGCAAAAUGGACCAUUAUGUGGCUACUACUGAAUUUCUUUGGUCUGUACCCUGUAGCCCUCAAAGUCUGGACAUUUCUUUCGCAAUACAUCCAGAGGAUGCAAAAGCUCUAUGGGACAGUGUCCACAAAACACCUGGGGAGGUUACCCAGGAAGAAGUUGACCUAUUCAUGGAUUGCCUUUAUUCACAUUUCCAUAGACAUUUCAAAAUUCAUUUAUCAGCCACAAGAUUAGUUCGUGUUUCAACAUCUGUAGCUUCAGCACAUACUGAUGGAAAAAUAAAGAUUCUGUGUCAUAAAUACCUUAUUGGAGUGUUAGCAUAUUUGACAGAACUGGCAAUUUUUCAAAUUGAGUGAAGCCUUAUGUGGACUAUAAGUUAUAGAUUAUAUACUCUUAUUGAUAACUUGCCUAAUUGCUAUGCUGAAAGAGACUGCAGGAGAAAUAGGCAUCUAUCUCUGCAUCUGUUUUCCCCACCAUGCCUUUGGAGUUGCCAAGAUGGAAGCCAAGAAGGAUCUAGAAGAACAAAGAAUAUGGUAGUAGAUGAGCCACAGCCAGGUGCCCAUGUACUAAUCAUGAUAACCUGACAUGCCAUUCUCAAAAUGCUGAGUUGUUAAUUUCUUGUCAUCUUUAAAUAUAUAUAUAUAGGCUGGGCUUGGUGGCUCACACCUGUAAUUCCAGCACUUUGGGAGGCUGAGGUGGGUGGAUCAUUUGAGGCCAGGAAUUCAAGACCAGCCUGGCCAACAUGGUGAAACCCCUUCUCUACUGAAAAUACAAUAAUUAGCUGGGCGUGGUGGCACAUGCCUAUGAUCCCAGCUACUGGGGAGGCUGAGGCAGGAGAAUCGUUUUAACCCAGAAGACAGGCUGCAGUGAGCCAAGACUGCACCACUGCACUCCAGCCUGGGCAACAAAGUGAGACUCUGCCUCAAAAAAUAAAAAAGAAAUAAAAUAAAUAAAUACAGCGUUUAUUAUGUUUAAACUCUUAGGAUUCAAAUGAGAUGUAUCUAAUGGAUAUUUCUGAUUUGGGUCUUUAAAACCUUUAAUCUCUUUUAAGCAUUUUAGACUUGCAUUCAGAAAGAAUUCUGUCUUCUAAAGACAUUUUCCUAGCAUUUCACUGCGGAGAACUGGCAAUCAAAAUCCCCUCAAAAGGGAACUAAAGAUUAAUAUACACAUUUUUUUAGUCAUUAAUAUGCUUCUGUUUUAAAUACAGUUCAACUCCUGUUGCAAUGUUGAAUUAAAUGUUUAUUUUAAAAUGAA